CAUAGAAAUGACUAGGUAUUUAAAAGGAUACUCGUCCGAGGGCAGGACUAUGGGAGGCUGCCCUGUACGGAAAAGAAGAAGAAAUGGCAGUAAAGAGGGCAACCAUCAUUCCACCCAGCCCAAAAGGAAUAAGAGAAACCCUAUCUUUCAGGAUUCUCAAGACACAGUUUUCAUGGAGUGAUAAUGAAAGGAGCAACAGCCGCCUUAAUAUCCCAGAGAGAGCAGGUGGACCAGAAGGCAACUUAAACCAGAUUGUUACUGAACCCAAUGCAAACUUUCCCCAGUUCUUGCAUGAGGGGUAUGUACCAUGCCAAGGUCUUUACUCCCAUAUCAACCAGACCUUGAAGGAGGCUCACUUCAACAGCCUGCAGCAGUGAGGGCAAGCUCCAACAUGAUGAAUUAGGACUUCCUUAUUCCAACCUAAACUGUGUUUAUAAAAGUAAUUGCAUACACACCAAAAAAAAAGUCUAUUGGUUUUUAAGACUAAAUUUUAAGUAACAAGUU